GCGCCAGCUCGUAGCAGGGGAGCGCCCGCGGCGUCGGGUUUGGGCUGGAGGUCGCCAUGGGGCGAGGCAGCGGCACCUUCGAGCGUCUCCUAGACAAGGCGACCAGCCAGCUCCUGUUGGAGACAGAUUGGGAGUCCAUUUUGCAGAUCUGCGACCUGAUCCGCCAAGGGGACACACAAGCAAAAUAUGCUGUGAAUUCCAUCAAGAAGAAAGUCAACGACAAGAACCCACACGUCGCCUUGUAUGCCCUGGAGGUCAUGGAAUCUGUGGUAAAGAACUGUGGCCAGACAGUUCAUGAUGAGGUGGCCAACAAGCAGACCAUGGAGGAGCUGAAGGACCUGCUGAAGAGACAAGUGGAGGUAAACGUCCGUAACAAGAUCCUGUACCUGAUCCAGGCCUGGGCGCAUGCCUUCCGGAACGAGCCCAAGUACAAGGUGGUCCAGGACACCUACCAGAUCAUGAAGGUGGAGGGGCACGUCUUUCCAGAAUUCAAAGAGAGCGAUGCCAUGUUUGCUGCCGAGAGAGCCCCAGACUGGGUGGACGCUGAGGAAUGCCACCGCUGCAGGGUGCAGUUCGGGGUGAUGACCCGUAAGCACCACUGCCGGGCGUGUGGGCAGAUAUUCUGUGGAAAGUGUUCUUCCAAGUACUCCACCAUCCCCAAGUUUGGCAUCGAGAAGGAGGUGCGCGUGUGUGAGCCCUGCUACGAGCAGCUGAACAGGAAAGCGGAGGGAAAGGCCACUUCCACCACUGAGCUGCCCCCCGAGUACCUGACCAGCCCCCUGUCUCAGCAGUCCCAGCUGCCCCCCAAGAGGGACGAGACGGCCCUGCAGGAGGAGGAGGAGCUGCAGCUGGCCCUGGCGCUGUCACAGUCAGAGGCGGAGGAGAAGGAGAGGCUGAGACAGAAGUCCACGUACACUUCGUACCCCAAGGCGGAGCCCAUGCCCUCGGCCUCCUCAGCGCCCCCCGCCAGCAGCCUGUACUCUUCACCUGUGAACUCGUCGGCGCCUCUGGCUGAGGACAUCGACCCUGAGCUCGCACGGUAUCUCAACCGGAACUACUGGGAGAAGAAGCAGGAGGAGGCUCGCAAGAGCCCCACGCCAUCUGCGCCCGUGCCCCUGACGGAGCCGGCUGCACAGCCUGGGGAAGGGCACGCAGCCCCCACCAACGUGGUGGAGAACCCCCUCCCGGAGACAGACUCUCAGCCCAUUCCUCCCUCUGGUGGCCCCUUUAGUGAGCCACAGUUCCACAAUGGCGAGUCUGAGGAGAGCCACGAGCAGUUCCUGAAGGCGCUGCAGAACGCCGUCACCACCUUCGUGAACCGCAUGAAGAGUAACCACAUGCGGGGCCGCAGCAUCACCAAUGACUCGGCCGUGCUCUCACUCUUCCAGUCCAUCAACGGCAUGCACCCGCAGCUGCUGGAGCUGCUCAACCAGCUGGACGAGCGCAGGCUGUACUAUGAGGGGCUGCAGGACAAGCUGGCACAGAUCCGCGAUGCCCGGGGGGCGCUGAGUGCCCUGCGCGAAGAGCACCGGGAGAAGCUUCGCCGGGCAGCCGAGGAGGCAGAGCGCCAGCGCCAGAUCCAGCUGGCCCAGAAGCUGGAGAUAAUGCGGCAGAAGAAGCAGGAGUACCUGGAGGUGCAGAGGCAGCUGGCCAUCCAGCGCCUGCAGGAGCAGGAGAAGGAGCGGCAGAUGCGGCUGGAGCAGCAGAAGCAGACGGUCCAGAUGCGCGCGCAGAUGCCCGCCUUCCCCCUGCCCUACGCCCAGCUCCAGGCCAUGCCCGCAGCCGGAGGUGUGCUCUACCAGCCCUCGGGACCAGCCAGCUUCCCCAGCACCUUCAGCCCUGCCGGCUCGGUGGAGGGCUCCCCAAUGCACGGCGUGUACAUGAGCCAGCCGGCCCCUGCCGCUGGCCCCUACCCCAGCAUGCCCAGCACUGCGGCUGAUCCCAGCAUGGUGAGUGCCUACAUGUACCCAGCAGGGGCCACUGGGGCGCAGGCGGCCCCCCAGGCCCAGGCCGGACCCACCGCCAGCCCCGCUUACUCAUCCUACCAGCCUACUCCCACAGCGGGCUACCAGAACGUGGCCUCCCAGGCCCCACAGAGCCUCCCGGCCAUCUCUCAGCCUCCGCAGUCCAGCACCAUGGGCUACAUGGGGAGCCAGUCAGUCUCCAUGGGCUACCAGCCUUACAACAUGCAGAAUCUCAUGACCACCCUCCCAAGCCAGGAUGCGUCUCUGCCACCCCAGCAGCCCUACAUCGCGGGGCAGCAGCCCAUGUACCAGCAGAUGGCACCCUCUGGCGGUCCCCCCCAGCAGCAGCCCCCCGUGGCCCAGCAACCGCAGGCACAGGGGCCGCCGGCACAGGGCAGCGAGGCCCAGCUCAUUUCAUUCGACUGACCCAGGCCAUGCUCACGUCCGGAGUAACACUACAUACAGUUCACCUGAAACGCCUCGUCUCUAACUGCCGUCGUCCUGCCUCCCUGUCCUCUACUGCCGGUAGUGUCCCUUCUCUGCGAGUGAGGGGGGGCCUUCACCCCAAGCCCACCUCCCUUGUCCUCAGCCUACUGCAGUCCCUGAGUUAGUCUCUGCUUUCUUUCCCCAGGGCUGGGCCAUGGGGAGGGAAGGACUUUCUCCCAGGGGAAGCCCCCAGCCCUGUGGGUCAUGGUCUGUGAGAGGUGGCAGGAAUGGGGACCCUCACCCCCCAAGCAGCCUGUGCCCUCUGGCCGCACUGUGAGCUGGCUGUGGUGUCUGGGUGUGGCCUGGGGCUCCCUCUGCAGGGGCCUCUCUCGGCAGCCACAGCCAAGGGUGGAGGCUUCAGGUCUCCAGCUUCUCUGCUUCUCAGCUGCCAUCUCCAGUGCCCCAGAAUGGUACAGCGAUAAUAAAAUGUAUUUCAGAAAGCA